AUUCCGCACCUCCGAGUGCUGGCCGGGCGAGAGGCUGGCGGCUGGGCUCUCGCGCCCCUCCCUGCAGGGCUCAGGCUCUCCCCCUCCUGUCUUCUCCGCGCUGUUCCUCGUCAUGGCGGCCCUCAGCAAGUCCAUCCCUCAUAACUGCUAUGAGAUCGGCCACACUUGGCACCCUUCCUGCCGGGUCUCCUUCCUGCAGAUCACCGGGGGCGCCCUGGAGGAGUCCCUGAAGAUCUAUGCUCCUCUGUACUUGAUUGCAGCAAUUCUCCGGAAACGGAAAUUAGACUAUUAUUUACACAAACUACUCCCUGAGAUCCUACAAUCCGCUUCAUUUCUAACUGCUAAUGGGGCCUUGUAUAUGGCUUUCUUUUGCAUUUUAAGGAAGAUACUUGGAAAAUUCUACUCAUGGACUCCUGGCUUUGGUGCCGCUCUGCCAGCAUCUUAUGUGGCCAUUCUCAUUGAAAGAAAAAGCAGGAGAGGGCUGCUCACAAUUUAUAUGGCCAACUUGGCCACAGAAACACUAUUCAGAAUGGGUGUAGCAAGAGGAACCAUCACAACAUUAAGAAAUGGAGAAGUCCUUUUGUUUUGCAUCACAGCUGCCAUGUACAUGUUCUUUUUCAGGUGCAAGGAUGGCUUGAAAGGAUUUACAUUUUCUGCACUUAGGUUCAUUGUAGGGAAGGAAGAAAUUCCCACACAUUCUUUUUCACCAGAGGCAGCAUAUGCAAAAGUGGAACAAAAGAGAGAGCAACAUGAGGAAAAACCCGGAAGAAUGAAUAUGAUUGGUCUAGUCAGGAAAUUUGUGGAUUCAAUAUGCAAACAUGGACCAAGGCAUAGAUGUUGCAAACAUUAUGAAGAUAAUUGCAUCUCUUAUUGCAUUAAAGGUUUCAUCAGAAUGUUUAGCGUGGGGUACUUGAUCCAGUGCUGCCUCCGAAUCCCUUCUGCAUUUAGGCAUCUGUUUACACAGCCAUCUCGGCUACUUUCUCUCUUCUACAAUAAAGAAAACUUCCAGCUUGGAGCUUUUCUUGGCUCUUUUGUUAGUAUAUACAAGGGUACUAGUUGCUUCCUGCGCUGGAUCAGAAACUUAGAUGAUGAACUACAUGCUAUUAUAGCUGGAUUUUUGGCAGGUAUAUCAAUGAUGUUUUAUAAAAGCACAACAAUUUCCAUGUAUUUAGCGUCCAAAUUGGUAGAGACAAUGUAUUUCAAAGGCAUUGAAGCAGGGAAGGUUCCCUAUUUUCCUCAUGCAGAUACUAUCAUCUAUUCCAUCUCUACAGCAAUUUGCUUCCAGGCAGCUGUCAUGGAAGUUCAGACUUUGAGACCAUCUUACUGGAAGUUCCUUUUAAGACUCACCAAGGGCAAAUUUGCUGUCAUGAACCGAAAAGUCCUUGAUGUUUUUGGUACUGGUGCAUCUAAACACUUUCAGGAUUUCAUCCCCAGGUUGGAUCCAAGAUACACAACUGUAACACCAGAGUUGCCCACAGAGUUUUCCUGAAGAUGACUGUAACUUAUUAAUGUGACUAAAUGUUUCAUCUUGAAGAGUUAAUUAUGUUGAACACAAAGGAGGGGGCCCAAGCUCGAACUUCAGUGUUAUUUCAGUUAGAGAUACUCUUUUCAUUUGUUUUGUUUUUCUUAUGAAUCAGAAAUUCAGAAGCUUUUUAGGAAGAUGUUGCUUAAUAAUUAAGCUUCCUCCAUAGCCAGAAUAAGAUUCUGGAUCACUGUAGUGACUGACAUUAUAUAUUAUUGAUCAAAUUAUGUCCACAAGCAAUAUUAUAUAAUCUACGUAGAAGUGUAAUAACAAACAAGAGUACACUUAAAAUUACUUUAAAAGAUGUCUUUAGUUCAUUCCAAUAUAAUUCUUGAUUAAAAUUAGGAUUAUUUCUACAUUUUAGGAUUUACAAAGGAUCACGGGUACAUGGAUUUGGUCUAUAUAUUUUUUUAAAGUUUUGAAUUGGUAUCUGUAGUAGUGGAAUGUUAUAGAUUUGAAGUAACUCUCCACGGACAGUGCUGCUUUCGUGUAGAGCAAUUUAAUUGGAGAAGUGGCCAUUCUUACUUCAGGGAUGCAAAGAUGGGUCUCAUACCAUUUGGAUAAAUGUCGUGGUAUCCAUGCUUUUUUUCAACUAAUAACAUCAUCUCUCUUCAUGACCAGUUAAUUGGGCUAUUUGGCAGCCCAGUGAACCUAUGUACUAAUGGCAAGUUAGGGGCAAAUGGAAAUGGACACAUCCGAUAAAGUUGAAAUGUAUGUUUUAAUCUUUCACAGAAGUAUUACACUUGAAUAUUUAAAAACAAAACUUUUAAACUUCCUAUAGGUUUAUGAUGUUUGUUUUCAUUUAUAUGGACAUAAUCCUUCAUAGCUCAGUUUAUAUGCCAUUGUUGUAUUAGAAGGGAUCAAAAUCCUAUGGAACAAAGUAGUCUUGGCAAGUUGGCAGUUUGUGUCCUCUCAGCUGUUUAACUUAUGUAAUGGAUGUUUUGCACCUGAAAACACUAUAAAAAUCCAGUGGUUGUUUAAAAAGUCCAUUUGUCACUAAUUCCAUUCAGGUUCUCCAACCUUCUUCUUGAAUAUCAUUGUCACCAUUUUUACUGUUAGAAUAAAGAGGUGACACCAUAAAGUCCUGCUGAUAAUGAGAGUAGUUCAGGACAGCUGUGAUUGAAAUAUGGUCGCUAUUUACAGUUUUUCAGGGAAAAGUUAUACUUUUCUAUGUUAAUAAAGAGCUGAAGUGGUCUACAGUUAAUGUGACAUGUAGGGAUGAUGAUAUUUUUAAAAUACAUUUUGUUGCUAAAAAGUUUUUAGGCCAGUGCAAAUUAUGCAGUAGAACUUGUGUUGCAAAAGGAAUUAUAACCCAUACUUUAAAAAUGCUUAAUCCCUCAUAUUCAAUUUCAUCAAGCCUUGUAUACUUCUGCUUAAAUGUAAUUCAAUCCUUGGUUGUUAUGGCAAACAGAAACCCAACAAAAAGACAGACUCUGGUACUAUGGUAACAGAGCCACUUUAUCAUUUGGUCAAAAUUUGGCAUUAUGAUUAGCUUUGUAGAACUGACCUGUUUAUUUGGCAAUGCUGUUAAAGGAUCAUUUCGGUUUCAGACUUCAAAGUUGAUUAAUAAAUUUAAUCUUAACUUUUUAUUCACUGGAAUCAAAACGAUGGUUGGUACUGUGUUUACUGUUUAAAAUGAAGUACUAAAGCCCUGAGAACUGCACCUCAUUUUCUUUAUCCAGAAAUUGUGCUUAUAUAUUUUCCUGUCAGGUUUAAAAAGAUGUUUUAAUUCAUAAAUUAUUGUUUUCAUUGACAUUAAAAGACUGUGAUAUUGAAAGAUGAAUUACGAAAUUUGCUGAGAUUGUUUAGUAAAAUUUUGCUGGUCAAAAAGGUGUAUUUCUACAAUUUACCUUUUCAUUUUUAUAAAUUGCAGUCAUUUUUUUAAAUUUUAUGUAAAAUGUAAAAUGAAAUAGCUAUCAUGAAGCAGAAUACAAUGAUGAAUGUAUAGGUUGAGUGAAUAACCAAUUUGCAGUGGUGGAUUGAGAAGUCCAGUUUGAUUUCAUUGGGACAGACUGCAAAGUGUAGUUGUUUGAGCAAACACAAAGAAACUUUGUGUUUUUGAAGACAAUCAGAAUGAUUACCUUUCUACCUCUAACUAAUCAGGUAUUGAUUGACAACUUUUUGGCAUUAUAAAUAAAGUAAAAUAGAUCUCUGCAUUCCAAAAUAUGUUUUUUAGUUUAUUUAUAUCCUGAAGAAAUGGUAAGUUUUCACUGGAACUGAUUACAGUAAACAAUAAUAUGUCCCCUUAGUCUUUCUGACAUUUUUAUAUAGAUUGAGAUUGAAAAACCGUGCAUUUGGGGCAGUGGUAUUAUGGUCAUUUCGUUGCUAUUUUCUGUUUUAAUAAAAUCCUAGAACUAGUAGCAACCGAGUAAAGAUUGAGUUUGCAAGAUAACAGAUUGUCUCAAAUCUAUUCAAUUCUCAGCAGUUUUUCAUCAAAUAAUUUCAGGAUCCAUUUUAUUACUCAUUUUUGAAGUAACACCUUUGGUUUAGUUUUAUUUUCCCAUAAAUUCUGCUUUUGCUUCUGUAACUUUUUUCUUGAACUAUAAGCAUAGUCAUCACUCAGUUGAUAUCUAGUUUAUUUUUUGCCUUCAUUCGUUGUUUAGUCAGUUGUUAUUUAAUUUAGAAUUUUAUAUUUUUUUGGCUCUCAGAUUUUAUAAUGAACUUUUAUUAGACUGAACAUGUAUGUUUUUGAUGGAAUCCAAACUGAGCAAAUGUCACACAGUAUUUUCUUGUUGUGCUCGAGUGUUCGUCUCCUUGUAGAUUGUAUCUAGGCUAACAUUUCAUUUAGUUGUUAAUGCUGACGUAAUUGUUUCCUGCUUAUAUUUUAUCAUAUCCCUGAGCUUCUGUGUGCUCUACAUUUCAUAGGUAAUGAAAAGCAAUGUCCUUUACUCUCAGGGAGCUUCGUCCACUUGCCUGUGUCACAACCUCUCCCUUGGUGCUAAUUAGGAAGCUUCUUGUGGGACUGAAGGGAACUGACCACUGGAGCAAUGGCCCAAAUGUUGUUUUUGGAGCAGAGAAAUUAUUAGCCCAGAGAUUCCUUAAAUUCUCCGUGUGAUUUAUUUUUUUAUUUUUUGAGUUGAGGUCUAGCUCUGUUGCCCGGGUUGGAGUACAGUGGUGCAAUCAUAGCUCAUUGAAACCUCAAAUUCCUUGGUUCAAGCAAUUAUUUCCCCUCAGUCUCUAAUAGCUGGGACAACAGGCAUGUGCCACCAUGCCUGGCUAAUAUUUAUUUUAUUUAUUUUUUUUUUGUAGAAACAAGGUGUUGCUAUGUUGUCCAGGCUGGUCUUAAACUCCUGGCCUCAAGUGAUCCUCUUGGGUUGGCCUCCCGGGACUCUGGGAUUCCAGGUGUGAGCCACGGUACCUAGCCAUAUUUUUAUUUGUAUGAGUAUUAAGUAGUUUGACACAGCAACAAAGUUGUCCUUUGUUUCCCAAAGGCAAAAGUAUACAUUUCUUACUAAGAUAUCUUAUAAACAUUCUCUCUCCUAACACCUCCUUCUAGUAAUCAUUUUCACAUAGUAGAAUACUUCACUCAGCUGAAAAUGAGUGGCCAAGAAAAAAAUACAAGAAAAGGAAUAAGAAGUGAUUAUUUUCUUUAGGGCUGCACUUUGAAUGUGAUGAGUAAUAAGGUUACCUUCAUUGUGGAGGUGAUGUUUACAAUUGCCUCCAGCCCUUUACUAUUGGUGCUGAAGCCACCAUUGGUGCCAGCUCUAUAAUUUCUUCUUCUUGUGGAAUUAACAAAGAAAGGAGUGUCAAGGACUGAGAUGACCCUCAGAUUGGGGGGCUGUCUUAGAUUCUAGGGCUUUGUAGUACUAUGUUUCUGUUUAAAGUAGUGGCCUCAGGUGACUUUGUAAUAGCCCUGUAGUUGCAAAAAGGGUAACUACAAAGAAAUGAAACUGACUCUAGUGUGUGUGACUUCUGGAAACAGAAGUGGGGCAGUAAGUUGGCCAUGAUAUAGCUAGUGUCAUAGGACUACAGCAGAGUAGUGAGUGAAUGGCCUUAAGCUUACAGCUGUGGUGAAUAAGAAUGUGUGCUAUUUUACACACAGAAGAAAAUGAUUGACUUUUGGUUGGAGGAAAGAAUUUAUAUCUGGUCUUUUGGAAAUUAUUCUGUUGCUGUUUUAUGUGGGCUCUCUCUCUCUCCCUCUCUCUCUCUCUCUGUCUGUCUCUCUUGCUGCUCCCUCUCCCUGCCACCUUGUCCAUUCUCUGCUUGCUGGUGUUACUUUAUGUUAACUAGUCUCCUUGGACUUCAUUGCAACCUUUUAAGCCAGCCGUUCAAGUGAGAGGCUCUGGAGUGAUCAUAACGGUGAUAACAAUGGAGUAAACAUUUCCAGAGACACUGAUUUUUUUUUUAUAUGCUCUGUUUUUCUUAGGCAGGAUGAUGUAGAAGAUAAUUGCACAGAUAUGGAAGGAGAUGUUUCUCUGUAUGUGAAGCCUUUAAAUCCAGAACAAUUAAUUUCUUCUCUUCUUAAAACCCCGUAACAUCACUUGACUCUGGAAUUUCCUAUUUUCUUUUACUUUCUCCAUUUUUUUUCCAUCUGUCCCUCCUACGAAUAUGUUUUACAUGAAAUAAUGUAUUGGGUUUUAUCUUUUGUCCCAGCAGACCUGAAAAUCCCAGUAUAUUACCACAGACACACAUACCAUCUGGUCACCAACAGGGACAUCAGGGCCAAGAGCAGUUUAUACUUCUUUCUUUAGCUCACAAACUACUAUAGCUUGCCUGUUCAGUUUUUUUUUUUUUUAAUAUUCAGUUUUGUGCCAUACUCUCCCCCACCCCCAGCCUGCUGCCUCUGCAGAGCAUAACAUUCUAAUCUUGUCAGACCGUGGAUAAUAGGAUGUUCCCUGGUCUUGGCAUAGAGGCCAUAGGCAUACAACAUGCUUUAUCUGCCUUGCUUAGACUCAGCAUCCCUUUCUGUCUUGAGAGAUUCAGGCUUCCAUAAAGUAGACCUGUAGACCUAUGUUGGCUGAGGUCACCCUGCAUUACUACUUUCCUCCAUCCCUGAACUAGGACCAGUUAAUUUUCGAAGUCUAGUUCUUCAGUGUCUAUUAAACUUUUUCCAGUAGUUAAUCGAUCUCUUAAAUUAAUUUUCUUUUCAGAUUAUUUUUGGUCACCUAAGAGGACCCUGAAGCUAUAGUGCCAAAGGUUUAAAGCAUGAAGUACAUUCUGUGGUUGGUCAUUAUGGGAUUGGAUGCCAAAAGGAAUGGGAGAGAAGAGACUAUAAACAUAUUUUAAGCCUUAUCUCUUUUCUCCUAUUCUUUUCUUUACCUUUCCUGGCCCAUGCUUUCCUGCCAUAUCUUUGCUAUGUAUUUCUUCAUCUUGAGCUCUCAAGGGAAAAAACAGGAGUCCUUAUUUUUCUAUUUAUUUCAGGGAAAAUUGAAGGUAAAUAAUAUCUGCAAAGCUUCAGGAAGAAAUUCAGUUGCAUCUGAAUCUGAGUCGGCAGUUUUUGAUAGCCUGUCACUGCUCAGGGAUAGCACUAAGGCUCUCUUCAGAACCAAAGGGCAGGAUAAAUAAAUCUAUGAAACUAGAGGCAUCAUUGAAUCAUCUGAGGACCUUUUUUUUUUUUUUUUUUUCACUAAAACGCUUCCUAUAACUUGGAUUAAAAUUCAAAAAUGGGAUUGCAGUCAUUGUUAAUUGCUCAACUAGUGGCAGUUUUUCCUUGCUGAGGGAACACUGAUGUUGUUUAAGACAGUUACAUGCCUAGCCCCAGGGAUGAAUCAUAAUUGUUCUAGGCCUUUCAUGUCUUUCCUUUCUUCUUGUCCAGAUACUUUUCCAACCAGCCUUUACUCGGAGGUGUUCAUGUGACCCUGUUUUGGCCAAUAAAAUGUAAUGGAAAAUCUGGGAAACACUUGGGAAAAAUCUUCCCUCUCUGCUUAAAGGAAAGUUCUUUUUACCUCUUUUUCUCUUGUUCAAGGUAUUAGUAUUAGUCAGUAGGGUCUGAAUCUGUGGCAGCAAUCUUGCAGACAUGAAAUGAAAAGUACAAACAUGAAAAACCAGCAUAUUAAAGAUGCCAGGUCAGAAAAAUAGAAAGAACCUGCUUCUGUGAGCCACUGAAUGGUGCCAUUAACCAUCUGCAUUUGAGCAUUUUGAGAAAAUAAACCUCUAUUUCUUAAAGUUCUGUAUCAGUCAGGGUUUCCCAGAGAGGCAGAACAAUAGGGAUAGAGAGAUACAUAGAGAGAGAUAUGAGAGGGAUAGAGAGAGACACAGAGAGAGAUAUGAGAGGGGAUUAAGGGAGUUGGCUCAUGUGAUUGUGGAGGCUGAGAAACCCCACCACAGGCCAUUCAUAACCUGGAGACCUUGGGAUGCUGGUGGUCUGGCUCAGUACAAGUCCAAAAGCCUUGGAACCAGGGAAACUGAUGGUGUAAUUCUCAGUCCAAGGCUGAAUUUUCAAGUCUGAGAACCUGGGGGUGGGAUGGGGGAGUGAUAGUUUUAAGUCCUGGAGUCCCAAGGUUAGAGGAUCUGGGGUCCUAAUGUCCAUGGGCAGUUGGAGAAGAGUGUAUCCCUGCUGCAGGGGAGAGAGAGAAGCCAAUUCUCCUUUCUUCUGUUUUUAUUCUACCCAGGCCUCCAGUGGAUUGGAGGUGCCUGCCCAUAUUGAGGGCAGAUCUUCUCUGCCUAGUCCACGCUAACUCACAUGCCAAUCUCCUCUGGAAACACCCUCACAGACACACCCCAAAAUAAUGCCUUACCAGUUCUCUAGAUAUUCCUUAAUCCAGUCAAGUUGAUGCCUAAAAUUAACCAUCACAGGCUUUAUGGCUCUAUUACCCAAGAAUUCUGUUACUUUCAGCUGAAAACAUUUCUAAUGGACAUAUUCCAAUUCUGUAUAGAUCAGAUCUCAGUUUCAUUUCCCAUUAUAUCCUUCUCUCUCUUGAUUUAGAAUUCUCUUUUUCUCCACUCUUCUGUGUAUGCUAAAAUACUGUCAAUCUCGUCUUUGAAGGUUUUGCUCAUCUUUAAAAAAUCUUAGUUGAUUAUGUUUUAUGUGUCAUUUAAUUAAGGAAUGAAUUUGCUUAUUUUUAUUUCAGUAGCUUUUGGGGUACAAGUGGUUUUUGGUUGCAUGGAUGAAUUGUAUAUUGGUGAAGUCUGAAAUUUUAGUGCACCUGUCACCAGAAUAGUGUGCAUUGUACCCAAUAUAUAGCUUUUUAUUCCUUCCCCUUCUGAGUCUCCAUAGUCCAUUAUAUCACUCUGUAUACCCUUGUGUAUCCAUAGCUUAGCUCCCACUUACAGUUGAGAACAUACAGAAUUUGAUUUUCUAUUCCGGAGUUACUUUACUUAGAAUAAUGGCCUCCAGCUCCAUCCAAGAUGCUGCAAAAGACAUUAUUUCAUCUUUUAUUUUUUAUGGCUGAGUAGUAUUCCAUGGUGCAUAUAUACCACAUUUUCUUUAUCCACUCAUUGGUCUAUGGGCACUUUGGUUGAUUCUGUAUCUUUGCAAUUGUGAACUGUGUUAACAAUAAAAAUAUAUAUACGAGUGUC